AUUUCCGGGCACGGCUUCCGGCGUCCUUCCCUCUCAGGGAAGCUCCAGCUGUCCCUCCCGCAGUUGGCCCUGUGGUGUUCCGAAGCCGGUUACGUACGGCCUGAGGGCCAGGCGAACCUCAGGCUCUUUGUCCUACUAAAAAGCGCAGCACAAUGGUAGAAGCAGAUCAUCCUGGCAAGCUUUUCAUUGGUGGCCUCAAUAGAGAAACCAAUGAGAAGAUGCUUAAAGCAGUAUUUGGGAAACAUGGUCCCAUAUCAGAAGUUCUUUUGAUAAAGGAUCGAACCAGCAAAUCCAGAGGCUUUGCAUUUAUUACUUUUGAGAACCCUGCAGAUGCUAAGAAUGCUGCCAAAGAUAUGAAUGGAAAGUCUUUGCAUGGAAAAGCAAUAAAAGUAGAACAAGCCAAGAAACCAUCUUUUCAAAGUGGUGGUAGGCGGAGACCACCAGCUUCUUCGAGAAACAGAAGCCCUUCAGGAAGUCUGAGAUCUGCAAGAGGAAGCCGUGGAGGAACAAGAGGGUGGCUUCCCUCACAAGAAGGGCACCUGGAUGAUGGUGGAUACACUCCUGAUCUCAAGAUGAGUUAUUCUAGGGGACUCAUUCCAGUUAAAAGAGGUCCAUCUUCAAGAAGUGGAGGUCCUCCUCCGAAAAAAUCUGCUCCUUCUGCUGUGGCAAGAAGCAAUAGUUGGAUGGGAAGCCAAGGUCCCAUGUCACAAAGAAGAGAGAAUUAUGGAGUUCCUCCACGCAGAGCGACAAUAUCUUCCUGGAGAAAUGAUCGCAUGUCAACAAGACAUGAUGGUUAUGCAACUAACGAUGGAAAUCAUCCAAGUUGCCAAGAAACGAGGGAUUAUGCUCCACCAUCUAGAGGCUAUGCAUACCGUGAUAAUGGUCAUUCUAAUCGGGAUGAACAUUCCUCUAGAGGAUAUAGAAAUCAUCGAAGUUCCCGAGAAACUAGGGAUUAUGCUCCACCAUCUAGAGGCCAUGCAUACCGUGAUUAUGGUCAUUCUCGUCGGGAUGAAAGUUAUUCUAGAGGAUACAGAAAUCGUCGAAGUUCCCGAGAAACUAGGGAGUAUGCUCCACCAUCUAGAGGCCAUGGAUACCGUGAUUAUGGUCAUUCUCGUCGACAUGAAAGUUAUUCUAGAGGAUAUAGAAAUCAUCCAAGUUCCCGAGAAACCAGGGAUUAUGCUCCACCACAUAGAGACUAUGCAUACCGUGAUUAUGGUCAUUCUAGUUGGGAUGAACAUUCCUCUAGAGGAUAUAGUUAUCAUGAUGGCUACGGUGAGGCCCUUGGUAGAGAUCAUUCUGAACAUCUAAGUGGAAGUUCUUAUAGAGAUGCACUUCAGAGAUACGCAACCUUAUUUCAGAAAACGGUGCAUAUUACUGCAGAAAUCACAUGGACAGGUCCAAAGCGGGGAGGAGGAGGAUGAGGAGGAAGAGGAGGAGGAGGAGGUGAAGAAGAAGAAGAAGAGGAAGAAGAAGUAGAAGAAGAAGGAGGAGGAGGAGGAAGCGGCAAGCUUUUAAGUCUAUACAUUAGUAUCACUGUGUCAGAAACUCAGUAGUCAUAGUGAAAUAAAAACAAUGAUCACAGUCAGUCAAUUCCAUCUCAUACCUAGACUGAAAUAUGAAACUUCUAAAGAAAAGAAAGUUAAGAACUUUGGGCAUAUCAAAAUGUUCCUAUACAGAUAAAAUUAUUGGUGACUUUUUCUCACUAGAAAACAUACAAUUCCAUGCUUUGUAUAUGUGUAAAUAAAAAUAUUUUUAUUUCCAUCAGUUAUGAUGUGCAAGCAAGUAAUAAAGUGAAAGUACACUAAUAAAAUGAUAUAAGGAAAUUUCUCUGUGUCAAAAAAUUCCAUUGAGGCCAUUAAUUUUACAAAAACCACGGAGAAUGCAUGGUGAAACUACACUAUACAGUACUUUUUAGUAUUUUACUUGCAUUUUAAAUAAUCAACAAAGGAAAGGAAAUUCUUAAUCAUUAUUUAUUACCAAUAACAUUAUUCUACUCGAAUAAUCCUUUUGAGAUUAAGUAUUUUAAAUAAAACUUUAAAAACAAAUUGUAUUGACUGAUACCAGCUUUCAAUGAAAUAACACUUCUGUAUUUGUAGUCAUGUGAAGUAUAAAUUUCUCCUCACAGUGGAUCUUUUAUAACACCAGUUUUAUUGAUUUCUCUGAUAGAAACCCUGUGAUAGCUCAUGCAUGGCUUUACUGUAACCAUACAUUACAUGACUCCAGAGAGUAGCCUUCAAAUAGAUGGAAAAAUUAUAUUUGUGACAAAAUUCUAAGAAAGGGAAUGGUAAAAUGGGAGAAUAAUUUCUAAAUUUCUAACUGUUCAUCAGUGGAUUUGGAUAUAUUUAGAUAUAGACAAAUAUUAGCACACUGCAAGUUUGCACAUGUGUAUAUAAAUUUAUAUGAGAUACCCAUAAUGUGUGGGUUGUGUAAUAUUUUAAUCCUCAAUUUUACAUGUGGGAAAUUUGGUAAGAGUUUAUCUUUAUCAAAUAAUCAAUUUGAAGUACUAUACUCAAUUUGAUGUAAAACCAACAAAAUCUCUGUCAACAUUCACUUUAAUUGAUCCAAUAAUGUUAACUGAUGAUAACUUCAUUCUCUUUGUCCCCUGUUGGCAGCCUGAAAGUUGAUUCUCACUCUAAUUCAUCACUCAAGGUGCCAUCCACAAGACACUAACUUUGCUGUGGAUUGUGACUUCUCACGCCAACACUUUUUUCCUGUAACAGUCCUACCU